AAGGGGUGGCGGCGACCGGAAGCGCAGUGCACACCCCCAUGGCCCGGGCUUUGGUCCAGCUCUGGGCCAUAUGCAUGCUGCGAGUGGCGCUGGCUACCGUCUAUUUCCAAGAGGAAUUUCUAGACGGAGAGCAUUGGAGAAACCGAUGGUUGCAGUCCACCAAUGACUCCCGAUUUGGGCAUUUUAGACUUUCGUCGGGCAAGUUUUAUGGUCAUAAAGAGAAAGAUAAAGGUCUGCAAACCACUCAGAAUGGCCGAUUCUAUGCCAUCUCUGCACGCUUCAAACCGUUCAGCAAUAAAGGGAAAACUCUGGUUAUUCAGUACACAGUAAAACAUGAGCAGAAGAUGGACUGUGGAGGGGGCUACAUUAAGGUCUUUCCUGCAGACAUUGACCAGAAGAACCUGAAUGGAAAAUCGCAGUACUAUAUUAUGUUUGGACCCGAUAUUUGUGGAUUUGAUAUCAAGAAAGUUCAUGUUAUUUUACAUUUCAAGAAUAAGUAUCACGAAAACAAGAAACUGAUCAGGUGUAAGGUUGAUGGCUUCACACACCUGUACACUCUAAUUUUAAGACCAGAUCUUUCUUAUGAUGUGAAAAUUGAUGGUCAGUCAAUUGAAUCCGGCAGCAUAGAGUACGACUGGAACUUAACAUCACUCAAGAAGGAAACGUCCCCGGCAGAAUCGAAGGAUUGGGAACAGACUAAAGACAACAAAGCCCAGGACUGGGAGAAGCAUUUUCUGGACGCCAGCACCAGCAAGCAGAGCGACUGGAACGGUGACCUGGAUGGGGACUGGCCAGCGCCGAUGCUCCAGAAGCCCCCGUACCAGGAUGGCCUGAAACCAGAAGGUAUUCAUAAAGACGUCUGGCUCCACCGUAAGAUGAAGAAUACCGACUAUUUGACGCAGUAUGACCUCUCAGAAUUUGAGAACAUUGGUGCCAUUGGCCUGGAGCUUUGGCAGGUGAGAUCUGGAACCAUUUUUGAUAACUUUCUGAUCACAGAUGAUGAAGAGUACGCAGAUAAUUUUGGCAAGGCCACCUGGGGCGAAACCAAGGGUCCAGAAAGGGAGAUGGAUGCCAUACAGGCCAAGGAGGAAAUGAAGAAGGCCCGCGAGGAAGAGGAGGAAGAGCUGCUGUCGGGAAAAAUUAACAGGCACGAACAUUACUUCAAUCAAUUUCACAGAAGGAAUGAACUUUAGUGAUCCCCAUUGGAUAUAAGGAUGACUGGUAAAAUCUCAUUGCUACUUUAAUCUAUGUUUCAAACUCAAA